GCUCGUUUUUCUCCCCGCCGCUGCGCUGGUAAGCCUGUGUUUUGGUUCGCUAUGGCCCGUACUAAGCAGACUGCUCGCAAGUCGACCGGCGGCAAGGCCCCGAGGAAGCAGCUGGCCACCAAGGCGGCCCGCAAGAGCGCGCCGGCCACGGGCGGGGUGAAGAAGCCGCACCGCUACCGGCCCGGCACCGUAGCCCUGCGGGAGAUCCGGCGCUACCAGAAGUCCACGGAGCUGCUGAUCCGCAAGCUGCCCUUCCAGCGGCUGGUACGCGAGAUCGCGCAGGACUUUAAGACGGACCUGCGCUUCCAGAGCUCGGCCGUGAUGGCGCUGCAGGAGGCCAGCGAGGCCUACCUGGUGGGGCUGUUCGAAGACACGAACCUGUGCGCCAUCCACGCCAAGCGCGUGACCAUUAUGCCCAAGGACAUCCAGCUGGCCCGCCGCAUCCGUGGAGAGCGGGCUUAAGAAGUGGCGGUUCGGCCGGAGGUUCCAUCGUAUCCAAAAGGCUCUUUUCAGAGCCACCCA